GCACUUUGUGGCAGCCACGCGAAGGCUCGAGGUCGCGAGCGUGUGCCCAGUCAGGGUCGGCUGCGGGUACUCGGCUUUGCGCUCUAUUUCGUUGUGGUCUGGCUGUUGAUCCGUAGGCACGCCUACGGCUAUUCCAUCAUGGCGAGGAUGGCGGUACUGUGGCGGAAGAUGAGAGAUAACUUCCAGAGCAAGGAGUUCCGGGAAUACGUGAGCAGCACUCACUUCUGGGGUCCCGCGUUCAGCUGGGGCCUUCCGCUGGCUGCCUUUAAAGACAUGAAGGCGUCGCCGGAGAUCAUCAGUGGCCGCAUGACAACAGCGCUCAUCUUGUACUCGGCGAUCUUCAUGCGCUUCGCCUACCGCGUACAGCCUCGAAACCUGCUGCUGAUGGCGUGCCACUGUACCAACGUGAUGGCGCAGAGUGUGCAGGCCAGUCGCUACCUACUCUACUACUACGGCGGCGGCGGCGCCGAGGCUAAAGCCCGCGACCCUCCGGCUACCGCCGCCGCUGCCACCAGCCCGGGUUCCCAGCCCCCGAAACAAGCUUCUUAAGAACUGAGAGGGCCUGAUCUCAUCUCUGCAGGUCACAAGCACUGAACUGCCAUUCCUCCUGAAAAAAGACCAAUGAAGACCUCGGUUUUGACUCUAAAACAGUGCGAAUCUGACUUAAACCUGCAGUUUGAUUAAUAAAGAAAUACAAAGUAACAUUGAA